AGGAAGUGACGCGCCUGGCCCGGGAGCUGCGGUCGCAGAGGCCGACGGAGCCGGAGUCGCGGACGCCGCGGGGUCUCCGGGACAGGAACCCUCAGUGCUGCGUCUAGAUUCUGCAGGGGAGGUUUGCUGGGACCUUGGCUCCACGCAGCCAGCGAAAUGGCAGCCACACUCGAUUUGAAAUCAAAGGAGGAGAAGGAUGCUGAGUUGGACAAGAGGAUCGAGGCUCUUCGGCGGAAGAAUGAGGCCCUCAUCCGGCGCUACCAGGAGAUUGAGGAAGACCGUAAGAAAGCUGAACUUGAGGGAGUCGCAGUCACAGCUCCCCGAAAGGGCCGCUCAGUGGAGAAGGAGAACGUGGCAGUGGAGUCGGAGAAGAACCUGGGUCCUUCCCGGAGGUCUCCUGGGACCCCUCGGCCCCCAGGGGCCAGCAAGGGGGGCCGGACUCCUCCACAGCAGGGAGGCCGGGCCGGCAUGGGCCGAGCAUCGCGCAGCUGGGAGGGCAGCCCCGGGGAGCAGCCUCGAGGAGGAGGAGCUGGGGGCCGUGGCCGGAGGGGCCGGGGCCGAGGUUCACCUCACCUCUCUGGAGCUGGAGACACCUCAAUCUCUGACCGUAAAUCCAAGGAGUGGGAGGAGCGGCGCAGGCAGAACAUUGAGAAGAUGAAUGAGGAGAUGGAGAAGAUCGCCGAGUAUGAGCGCAACCAGCGGGAAGGGGUUCUUGAACCCAACCCAGUGCGGAACUUCCUGGACGACCCCCGGCGACGCAGCGGGCCCCUGGAGGAGUCUGAGCGGGACCGCCGGGAGGAGAGCCGCCGGCACGGCCGCAACUGGGGGGGCCCCGACUUCGAGCGGGUGCGCUGUGGCCUUGAGCACGAGCGGCAGGGCCGCCGAGCUGGCCUGGGCAGUGCUGGAGACAUGACGUUGUCCAUGACGGGCCGGGAGCGGUCGGAGUACCUGCGCUGGAAGCAGGAGAGGGAGAAGAUCGACCAGGAGCGGCUGCAGAGGCACCGCAAGCCCACUGGCCAGUGGAGGCGCGAGUGGGAUGCCGAGAAGACCGAUGGGAUGUUCAAGGAUGGCCCAGUCCCUGCCCAUGAACCAUCCCACCGCUAUGAUGACCAGGCCUGGGCCCGGCCCCCGAAGCCCCCUACUUUUGGGGAGUUCCUGUCCCAGCACAAAGCUGAGGCCAGCAGCCGCAGAAGGAGAAAGAGCAGUCGGCCCCAGGCCAAGGCAGCGCCCAGGGCCUACAGUGACCAUGAUGACCGCUGGGAGACAAAAGAAGGGGCAGCAUCCCCAGCCCCUGAGACUCCACAGCCUACUUCCCCCGAGACUUCCCCCAAGGAGACACCCAUGCAGCCACCCGAGAUCCCAGCUCCUGCCCACCGGCCUCCUGAAGACGAGGGGGAAGAGAAUGAGGGGGAAGAGGAUGAAGAAUGGGAGGACAUAAGUGAGGAUGAGGAAGAGGAGGAGAUCGAGGUGGAAGAAGGUGAUGAGGAGGAACCAGCCCAAGACCACCAAGCCCCAGAGGCUGCCCCCACCGGGAUCCCCUGCAGUGAGCAGGCCCACGGAGUCCCCUUCAGUCCGGAGGAGCCCCUGCUGGAGCCCCAGGCCCCUGGCACGCCUUCCAGCCCUUUCUCACCACCCAGCGGCCACCAGCCUGUGUCCGAUUGGGGUGAAGAGGUGGAGCUGAAUUCUCCCCGGACCACUCACCUGGCUGGCGCCCUCUCCCCGGGAGGUGGCCAGUCAGCCCCUGCCUUCCCGGAGAGUGGGCCCAGCCUCCGAGGAACCCAGGAAGCUGAAGAGGAAGGGUCUGAGGCAACUCCAGAGGCAGGCCCCGAAGGCCAGGAGACGGCGGAGAUCACCGACUUCCAGAGGGCCUCCCCGAAUUCCUGAAGACGCUGCUGGGAGGGGACUGAAGCUUCCCCGCCUUGAUGGGGAGGGGGCGUGAGGAGGGGUUUAUCUGGAUUUCCAGGCUGUGUUCUUUCUACCCCAGAGCCUAGUCUGGACCCCUUGGCUCUAGGGAGAGGGAAAAGCUGACCGUUGGGGAGGAGCUGGGAGAAGGGGCGCGAUUGCGGUGAGGGGCGGAGCUGGAACCUCGGGGCCUGAGGUGCUGAGGAUACCUGAAAGCGGGCUGAGAGUGUGCUGGAGGAGGCGGGUCCCGCGGGGGCGGAGCUAGGCUGCCUGGGCGGGGCCGGAAUCCUGACAGGCGGAGUUAGAGCGGGGGGCGGGGUCAGCGCGCGCGGGUGGGGCUCUGGCCAUGGGCAUGGGGCGGGGCCGUCAGCGGGGGCGUGGUCGGGGUGUCGCGCGGGAACCCGCGCGGGAGGAGAGCGGGGAUUCCGGAACUAGAGUGUGGGAGCCAGAGGCCGUAGCGGGCAGGGCUCGAGCACUGGAGUAGAGCAGUCCGACAGGUAGAGAAGUGAGACUGGCUGCGGCACAGGGCGGGUUAGGGCUCCAGGCAGGGCUUGAGCGGGACGAGGGGGCGGGCUCCGAGGCGGGCUAGAUGCCUGGGCUGGAUGAAGUCCGAGUCUGGGAAGAGAACCGUGUUGUGGCGGGAGGAGGCGGUGAUUGGGGUGGUGGGGCUAAGCGCGGGGGCGGGGCUGGAGCGAGGGGGGCGGGGUAGCACCUCCGCCUGUCGGUGGUGGGGCGGAGGCUGGAGGGGGUGGGCCUAGGAUGCGGAGGCGGCAGCUCGCGUGGGGGCGUGACCAUGCUGGCGGGGGCGGGGCCGGAGGCGGGCGGUUUAGAGAGCGGGGCGGUCUGCGGGGUGGGGGCGGGGCCUGGUGGGGGCGGGGCCUGUGCGGUCUGCGGCGCGGAGCCGAGUGGGCUGCGGGGAUGCGGGGGACCAGCUGCGUGGGCGGCGGCGCCGAGAGCCCCGGAGGCGCGGGGCUGAGCGAGGGCCCGCGGGGGCGCUGGCUGCGCUUGGCUCCGGUAUGCGCCUACUUCCUCUGCGUCUCGCUAGCUGCCGUGCUGCUCGCCGUGUACUACGGUCUCAUCUGGGUACCCACGCGGUCUCCCGCGGCACCCGCCGGCCCACAGCCCAGCGCGCCGUCCCCUCCGUGUGCUGCCCGCCCGGGCGUGCCGCCUGUCCCGGCGCCCGCCGCUGCCUCCCUCUCCUGCCUCCUGGGAGUCCCCGGCGGGCCGCGACCCCAGCUCCAGCUGCCGCUGAGCCGCCGCCGCCGCUACAGCGACCCUGACCGCCGUCCGAGCCGCCAGACACCCAGAGAGACGCCAGAGGCCGCGGAGGGGCGAAGACCCGGGUAACUCUCCCUUCCACCCCAACCCGGAUCGCCAGCCCUCGAGAGCUCUGUGCUCCACGCCGAGGAUGCACCGUCUCUGGAUUGGUCCGGCCUUCUUCCUAAUGACAUCGCUCAGCGUCUCUGGAGCCGUCAUCCCGCGGAAUGGGGGCCCAGGGGGUGUCAGCUCGGGGCCUUGCCUCUUGCAGCUACUCUGUGGUCAGGCCGGGUCCUCCACCAUCAGGAAGAUCCCAUCCUGAGCUCUGUCUCCUGCCCCUCCUGCUGUGGGAUGCUGAGCACAGAGCCCACAGCCCAUCUGCCUCUUCACCUCCCUGAAUCCGUGUCCAUCUGCAAUAAACGACAGCCUCGGCUGCCUCGUGCUGUGUCUGUCCUGUUGUCUGCA